ACUUCAGUUUGGACAACUACUCACAGCUACUACACAGAGACCCGAACGAGUCACUGAUAUACACCUGGACCACCACCAAUGGAUAUACAAAUGGCAAACAAUUUUACUCCGCCCUCUGCAACUCCUCAGGGAAAUGACUGUGACCUCUAUGCACAUCACAGCACGGCCAGGAUAGUAAUGCCUCUGCAUUACAGCCUCGUCUUCAUCAUUGGGCUCGUGGGAAACUUACUAGCCUUGGUCGUCAUUGUUCAAAACAGGAAAAAAAUCAACUCUACCACCCUCUAUUCAACAAAUUUGGUGAUUUCUGAUAUACUUUUUACCACCGCUUUGCCUACACGAAUAGCCUACUAUGCAAUGGGCUUUGACUGGAGAAUCGGAGAUGCCUUGUGUAGGAUAACUGCGCUAGUGUUUUACAUCAACACAUAUGCAGGUGUGAACUUUAUGACCUGCCUGAGUAUUGACCGCUUCAUUGCUGUGGUGCACCCUCUACGCUACAACAAGAUAAAAAGGAUUGAACAUGCAAAAGGCGUGUGCAUAUUUGUCUGGAUUCUAGUAUUUGCUCAGACACUCCCACUCCUCAUCAACCCUAUGUCAAAGCAGGAGGCUGAAAGGAUUACAUGCAUGGAGUAUCCAAACUUUGAAGAAACUAAAUCUCUUCCCUGGAUUCUGCUUGGGGCAUGUUUCAUAGGAUAUGUACUUCCACUUAUAAUCAUUCUCAUCUGCUAUUCUCAGAUCUGCUGCAAACUCUUCAGAACUGCCAAACAAAACCCACUCACUGAGAAAUCUGGUGUAAACAAAAAGGCUCUCAACACAAUUAUUCUUAUUAUUGUUGUGUUUGUUCUCUGUUUCACACCUUACCAUGUUGCAAUUAUUCAACAUAUGAUUAAGAAGCUUCGUUUCUCUAAUUUCCUGGAAUGUAGCCAAAGACAUUCGUUCCAGAUUUCUCUGCACUUUACAGUAUGCCUGAUGAACUUCAAUUGCUGCAUGGACCCUUUUAUCUACUUCUUUGCAUGUAAAGGGUAUAAGAGAAAGGUUAUGAGGAUGCUGAAACGGCAAGUCAGUGUAUCGAUUUCUAGUGCUGUGAAGUCAGCCCCUGAAGAAAAUUCACGUGAAAUGACAGAAACGCAGAUGAUGAUACAUUCCAAGUCUUCAAAUGGAAAGUGAAAUGGAUUGUAUUUUGGUUUAUAGUGACGUAAACUGUAUGACAAACUUUGCAGGACUUCCCUUAUAAAGCAAAAUAAUUGUUCAGCUUCCAAUUAGUAUUCUUUUAUAUUUCUUUCAUUGGGCACUUUCCCAUCUCCAACUCGGAAGUAAGCCCAAGAGAACAACAUAAAGCAAACAACAUAAAGCACAAUAAAAAUGCAAAUAAAUAUUUCAUUUUUAUUUGUAAACGAAUACACCAAAAGGAGGCGCUCUUAAUAACUCCCAAUGUAAAAAGUUUUGUUUUAAUAAAAAAUUUAAUUAUUAUUUCUUGCCAACAAAUGGCUAGAAAGGACUGAAUAGAUUAUAUAUUGCCAGAUGUUAAUACUGUAACAUACUUUUUAAAUAACAUAUUUCUUAAAUCCAAAUUUCUCUCAAUGUUAGAUUUAAUUCCCUCAAUAACACCAAUGUUUUGUUUUGUUUCGUUCUGGGUCAUAAAACUUUGUUAAGGAACUCUUUUGGAAUAAAGAGCAGGAUGCUGCAAA